GUCCACUUCGUCGCGACUCUCCAACACCUAUUUUCUCCAGGAGCUGCUUCGGACCCGUUUGUUUUUUUUGUUUCGUUUUGUUUUGUUUUUCUGACAGCGACAGCCCUUGGGCAACGCUAAUCAUUCCAAGCAAAUUCUGUCAUGCCAAGACCUCCCUUAACAGCACGCGCCCACUUGUUUCCAACUCUCCUGCGAAUUGGGCUUCGGGAGCCUCCGAAACCAAGGCUCGGAGAUGUGGAGCGCACAGGGGAAGGGUCGAGCUGGGACCCACACCCGGCUCUUCCUCCCACACCGCCUGUUGAGCCCAAGGCUCAAUUUCAACACAAAGCUCUCCUUCCCUCAAUUCCUUCAACGACGGGUAACCUUCAACGAACACCUACCGGACCAGAACAGAGUGUACGAGCGGCGCGGGAAGGUGGCACAAAGGCAUGGCCCAGAGGAGUGGCAGGAAGACUCAGCCGGGGCCCUCCACUCCCCAGCCUGCCCGGCCUGGGCAGAGCCGCCGGGCCGCCCGAGUCCUGGGGCUCGCGGAGGAACGGAGAUGGCCUCCGCAGGGGCUCGCGGAAGCCCCCAGGGCGUCGGACCGUCUCACGCGCGCGUCCCGCGCCACUCACCUGUGGGACCCAUAGCGUCGCCCGCUUCAGAGGUGGAAGCCGCCAUUCCGCCACCGCGCCAAAACGUCGUCAUCAAGCUGCGCGCAGAGCCACGCCCCGCGGCCGGGCGGGAAAAGCGCUUCUACCUCUUUGGGCCGUUACCUCAAAAGGCUUGAGUGACAACUUGAGGACAAGGCGGCGCCUCAACAAGAUUUCACACAGCAGCUACGGGGGCCAGAGAAGCAGCACCGCAUGGUGUGGCAGGAGAAGGAGGACAUGCACAAGCAAUUGGUUGAAGCUUCAGAGACAUUGAAAUCCCAAGCCAAAGAACUGAAAGAUGCCCAUCAGCAGCAAAAGCUGGCCCUGCAGGAGUUCUUGGAGCUCAAUGAGCUCAUGGCAGAGCUCUACUCCCAGAAGCAGAAGGUGUGGGACAAGGAGGAGGAGAUGGAAGUAGCCAUGCAGAAAGCUGACAUGAUGUGGCAGGAGAUCUGAAGAUCCAAGAAGCUCAGAAAGAGGAUGCUGUUUAGCCAGAUGCGGUGGCUCACGCCUGUAAUCCCAGCACUUUGGGAGGUCGAGGCGGGUGGAUGGCCUGAGGUCAGGAGUUUGAGACCAGCCUGGCCAACAUGGUGAAACCCUGUCUCUAUUAAAAAUGCAAAAAUUAACCAGGCAUGGUAUUGGGUGCCUGUAAUCCUAGCUACUUGGGAGGCUGAAGCAGGAGAAUUGCUUGAACCUGGGAGGCGGAGGUUGCAGUGAGCCAAGAUCAUGCCACUGCACUCCAGCCUGGGCAACAAGAGCAAAACUCUGUCUCAAAAAAAAAAAAGGGGGGGAGGAAGCUAUUUAGAUAUUUCAGCGAUGGUAUUGACUGGACUUUUGUAUGACCUUAAUAAAACAUCUUUGAAAA